AGCCGAGUCUGAGCAUCUCGGAGGAUGCGGCGCGGCGAUCGGCUGCAGGGACGCGCGCAAGGUGAACACGGGGGCUGCGGCGCGCAGGUGAGGAGCUGGCCCAGGGAGGGGGCGAUGGCGGGACCCCGACGGGGAGCGUGGCCUGCUGCCCCCGUCGCGGGCGCAGGCGACCAGGCCUGCACGGCGCCCACCCCCAUCCAGGACACUGCGGGAAGGCGCGGAGCCAGGGAGAGAGGAGACGGAGGAGGAGGAGGAGGAGGAGGAGAGGUAACCCGAGAUGGACCAGCUCCGAGGCUGCCCCGCAACGGCCUCGCCCUGCCCCCAGGCCGGCCUCUCCCCAGUCCCUGCGGCAGAGAGAUCCGCCACCCCCCACAGCCUCUCCAGCAGAGUGGGAGCCCAGGGCUGGGCAAGCCCCCGCCUUGUCCGCAGGUGCCCACAUCUCUUGGGUUGGCAGUGGUAGGCAGAUGGCAUGUUUAUCUUUGGAGGCCCCAUUCAGCCGUUUUCUCGGCAAAGCUUUUUGGACCUCCUGUGGAAGAUGAGCCUCCGAGGGUUUCACAACCCCGAUUGUGUCCACUCAGCUGUGUGACCUUGGGGGAGUUGCUCACCCUCUCUGAACCCCCGUUUCUUCCCCCUGUGAAAUGGCUGUUCCCACACCUUGUAUUGGGAGGGCGGAGUGACGUGUUGCUAAGCUCAGCGCAGGAGCCUCACUGGGAAAGAACUAAACACAGGAGCACUGUUUUUAGCCAGUACCUGUGUUAGGGGCGUCUCAGCGCACCCCUACUCCCAACCCUGGAGCAAAGCCCUGUCUCUGGGCCCCCAGCACCUAGCCUAGACCAGGAGCAGCCCAUGGGGCUCCGUGAAUGUUUGAGAAAUGAACUAACAAGGCUUUAAGACAGAGUCUAAACUCGAGUUUGGAGGAUGGGACUCAAAGGUCUUUGAACCCCUUGAAAUUGUUCACAACUUUCGGUGAGCCUGGGUCUUUUCCCCGGGAGAGCACCAGGGGUUUUCAGUGGCUUCUUAAGGUGUCUGUGAGCCACCAUGGGUUAACAGCCAGGAAGCUUUGGGGACAGCUGCUCCCCAGAGAGGAAAAGAGCAGGGCCUCUGCCGCCAAACACACCCAGGCUUCAGCUCUCGCACCCUCCAUGAAACCUCUCCUGGUGGUGGGGCCCCUUCCUGCCUCCCUGGCCCACUGACAGGCUCUCGAGAACAGGAACUUUUAGGGGAUAUCCACGUGGGGCCAGGUAUAUACUGGAGGCUGCAGGUUUGAAAUAAGAGGCAGGAGAUUAUUAUAGAAUCAGACCAGAGUGACAAGUGCCCAGGAAGAUGAGGGAAGGAAGGCGGGAAGAGGAAUGUGUAACGCUUGUCAAGCAUCAGGUAUGAACCUCGCCCAUACCUGUUUGGUUAUUUGUCUCAUGCCUUGAGUUAGGCAUGCUUAUUAUCCCCAUUUUACUGAUGGGAAAACUAUGAUGCAGAGAGGUGAAAUGACUCCCCCAGGAAAUGAAGACACUGGGAUUCAAACUCAGGCCCCUCGCCAAAGGCCGGUGCAUAUUCCUCUCCCUCUCCACGUCUCUCAUUUUUGAAGUGGGCCUUUAGGAAUAACAUUUCAGGCAGGGUGCAGUGGCUCAUGCCUGUAAUCCCAGCACUUUAGGAGGCCAAGAUGGGCAGAUUACCUGAGGUCAGGAGUUCAAGACUAGCCUUGCCAACAUGGCAAAACCCCAUCUCUAUUAAAAAUAUAAAAAUUAGCCAGGUGUGGUGGCACAUGUCUGUAACCCCAGCUACUCGGGAGGCUGAGGCAGGAGAAUCACUUGAACCUGGGAGGUGGAGGUUGCAGUGAGCCGAGAUCACGCCACUGCACUCCAGCCUGAGCGACAGAGCAAGACUCCGUCUCAAAAAGAACAGGAUUUCAGUAAGUGAAGGGGAAGGGAGAGAGCAUUCCCUGCUGACAGAACAGCAGAAGCAAAAGGCAUGGGAGCCACACAGUCCAGUGGGUGUUGGAGGACAGAUGAACAGCUUGUGGUGGCCAGGGUCUUGGAAGGCCAGGAGAGGAGCUUAUGUUCUUUCUUGAGGGAAAUGGGGAGCCACUGAAGGUUUUAAAGCAGGGCAAGUGCCACGUCCAGCAAUUUUAAAAGCAGAGAAGCUGCUGCCUUGCGUUGCUUUUCUUUCCUGUCAGCCCCUUGAGGAAGGCAUGGGGGCCCCCAGCCCUCACAUGUCAUUCCAUGCCCUGUUUUUUUUUUAGGCUCAUCCAGUGAGGACUGGAAGGUGGGGGCUUUAGGCCCAGGCAUCGGAGUAGACCAUGGCCUCCAGCCCAUGGGGCUGUGUAUGUGGCCUUCUGCUGUUGCUGCUGCCACUCCUGGGGACUGGCCCUGCCCUGGGGAGGGGCUUUCCCAGGCCACUUGAAAACUCCGAAAUCCCUAUGAUCCCUGGAGCCCACCCCAAGGGCUCUGUGGGCUCAGAGCCCCAGGCCUUUGACGUGUUCCCGGAGAACCCCAGAGCUGACAGUCACAGGAACUCUGAUGUCCGCCACGCCCCUGCUGAAGAGAUGCCUGAGAAGCCUGUAGCCUCUCCCCUUGGCCCAGCCCUGUACGGGCCCAAAGCAGCACAAGGAGCUCAGAGAGAACGACUCCCAGUAACUGAUGACCUCCAGAUGGCUCAAGGACCAAGCUCCCACGGCUGGACAGGACCUCUGGACUCACAAGAGCUUCUGCAGCAAGAAGCAGUGGCUCCCCACCCAGUGGGCCACCCUCAUCUCACUUUCAUCCCCACAACUCCCAGACGUCAACUCAGGGUAGCCACAGUUCCUCCCUCCCUGCAGCAUGAAGGCCAAGAGGGACAGUGGCCACCUAGAGAUGAGGGUCUGAAGGCCAAAACUAAGAGCAGGGUCCCACCCACUUCUCCCUCAGACCACCAGGGCCCACCCCACACCCUUGUUUCCCACUCAGGUACUGUCAAGAGGCCAGUGCUGGAAGGACAGGGUGGGUUUGAGGAACACUUGCAGGAGGCAGCUCAAGGUCCCCACUUCACCCAGCAGGAUCCAGCAGCCCCUGAUGUUGGCUCAGUACCCCCAGUUGAGGUGGUGUACUCUCAGGAGCCAGGGGCCCAGCCAGACUUGGCAUUGGCCAGAAGCCUUCCUCCUGCUGAGGAGCUGCCGGUUGAGACCCCCAAGAGGGCUGGCGCUGAGGUGUCCUGGGAAGUCAGCUCCCCAGGUCCCCCGCCCAAGCAGGCUGACCUUCCUGACGCUAAGGAUUCACCAGGACCCCAGCCCACGGAUCCACCCGCCUCAGAGGCUCCUGAUCGGCCGUCUAAGCCAGAGAGAGCAGCAAUGAAUGGAGCAGACCCCAUCUCCCCCCAGCGGGUGAGAGGAGCUGUGGAGGCCCCAGGCACCCCCAAGUCUCUCAUCCCUGGUCCCUCAGACCCUGGCCCAGCUGUAAACCGAACAGAGAGCCCCAUGGGGGCCCUGCAGCCAGAUGAAGCCGAGGAGUGGCCGGGGCGCCCCCAAAGCCAUCCCCCAGCACCCCCAGUCCAGGCCCCCUCGACGUCACGCCGGGGCCUCAUUCGAGUCACCACGCAGCGAGCCCUGGGCCAGCCUCCCCCUCCGGAGCCCACCGCCAGCUCCAUGGCUUCAGCCCCAGCCUCCAGCCCCCCAGCCAACGCCACUGCACCCCCGCUACGCUGGGGCCCCCUUCGGCGGGUCCUGAGCUUCUCCUGGGAGCUGCACGUCUACGGGGUGGGGGUACUCUUUCUGCUGCCCGCGUUGUUGGCGCUGGCUGCGCUGGCAGCCGCCCCAGCAGGGCCCCGGCUGGCAUUGGUGGCCGCGGUGCUGGUGCUCGUGGCUUCGGCGCUGCGAUCCGCCUACAUGCUUACCGACCCUUACGGCUCGCAGGCGCGGCUGGGCGUUCGCGGGGGCCUGGUGCUCUACAACCUGCCCUUCCCCUUGCUGCUUACGGCGCUGGCAGCCCUGACUCUGCUCGGCCUGGGCGCGGGGCUGCCGCCACCGCUGCAAAACCCACUCCUGCUGGGAGCAGUGGCGCUGGUGCAUGGUGUAGGGUUGCUCGCGACAGACCUGCUGUCCACAUGGUCUGUGCUCAACCUCCUGACGCAGGGCUUGUCGUGCGCCUGGGGCGCGGCCGUGGCUCUGGGCACGCUCUGCCUGUGCCGUCGCCGCCUGCUGGACGGCCCACGGGGCUGGGAUGCCAGCCCGGGCCCUCGGCUGUUGGCUGUGGCGGGCGCGCUGGGGCUGCUGGCUAGCGGCUUGCAGCUGGCGGCUGCGCUCUGGCUGUACCCGGGCCCAGGCCGCGUGGGCCGCUUCUCGUGGGCCUGGUGGGGUGUCCACUUCUGGCUGCGCCUCCUGGAGCUGACAUGGGCGCUCGCCCUGGCGUUGGCCGCGGUGGCUGCCGCGAGACCCAGGCCGCCCACGGAGCACGCUUGCUGGGCUAAGCUGAUGCGUCUGGCGUGCCCGGCGCCGUCAGGAAAGAGCGAGGUGCCGGAGCGACCCAAUAACUGCUAUGCAGGGCCCAGCAACGUUGGUGCAGGCAGCUUGGACAUCAGCAAGAGCCUCAUCCGCAACCCGGCGGAGAGUGGGCAGCUGGCCACGCCCAGUUCAGGCGCCUGGGGCUCGGCUGCGUCGUUGGGUCGCGGACCCCAGGGUGGCCCGGGACUGUCCCGCAACGGUGUGGGACCGGCGCCAUCGCUGAGCGAGCUGGAUCUGCGGCCGCCAUCGCCCAUCAACCUGAGCCGCAGCAUCGACGCCGCGCUCUUCCGCGAGCACCUAGUGCGAGACAGUGUGUUCCAGCGCUGCGGCCUCCGCGGCCUGGCCUCCCCGCCGCCUGGAGGCGCUCUGCGGCCGCGCCGGGGCAGCCAUCCCAAAGCCGAGCUCGACGACGCUGGCUCCUCGCUCCUCCGCGGCCGCUGCAGGUCGCUCAGCGACGUGCGCGUGCGCGGGCCGGUCCCACAGCACGUAGUGGAAGCACCCGACGGGGCAGCCGCUGCGGCUUCUGGCAGCUCCCUCGACAGCUUCUCCAGGGGUUCACUCAAGAUCAGUUGGAACCCCUGGCGCCACGGGCUGUCAUCAGUGGACAGUCUGCCCCUAGAUGAGUUGCCCAGCACGGUACAGCUACUGCCUGCCCCGACCCCAGCCCCUGAUUCUACCGCCGCUCGGCAGGGGGACGGCCAGGGAGAGGUCCAGCCGCGCGGCAAGCCUGGGGAAUCCCGCAGCGCCUCCAGUGAUACCAUCGAGCUUUGAAGAGCGGUCCUGACGCAGGGCCAGGACCCUGCCCGAUGCCCACAUGGCAUGGCCUACUGGGACAGUUGAGCCUUUAAAAAAUGGGCAUCCUGGCCAGGCGCGGUGGCUCACGCCAGGAAUCCCAGCACUUUGGGAGGCCGAGGUGGGUGGAACACGAGGUCAGGAGUUCGAGAUCAGCCUCCUGGUCUCGAACAUAGCGAAACCCUCGUCUCUACUAAAAAUACAAAAAAAUUAGCCAGGUGGCACACGCCUGUAGUCCCAGCUACUCGGGAGGCUGAGGCGGGAGAAUUGCUUGAACAGGGAGGCAGAGGUUGCAGUGAGCCGAGACCACGCCAUUGCACUCCAGCCUGGGUGACAAGAGUGAGACUCCGUCUCAAAAAAAAAAAAAAAAAAAAAAAAAAAAAAGGCAUCCCCAGGCCUCUCUACCUGACGGCAACCCCCGGGGGACAGCCAGGUUUGAACUCACCCCACCCCCAUGCCGUUUUUUGCUUUUAAUAUUUCUAUUUUUUUUUCAGCCGGCAUUUUGCACAGAGGCCGUGUCUUAUGCGGAAUACAGGGUGGGUGUGCAUGGAUUCGGGCAUGAAGAACAGGGAGCAGGUGCCCCAGACUCCCCAACGUGGAGUGAUGAGCCUCGCUUGUCUAGAUUGUCCUCUUUGUGCCAAAGAAAUAAACCCUUAGGACUUGG